AGCCUCGGCCCGGACUCGCCGCCAACGAGGAGCCGAGCGCCCUGGAGAACGCGUCGGGGCUGAGCCGGGGUCCAGCAGCCGCCGCUAUGGACAUCCCGCCGCUGGCCGGCAAGAUCGCGGCGCUGUCGCUGAGCGCCCUCCCGGUGUCCUACGCGCUCAACCACGUCUCGGCGCUCUCGCACCCCCUGUGGGUGGCAUUGAUGAGCGCCCUAAUCCUGGGUCUGCUUUUCGUGGCGGUCUACAGCUUGUCCCAUGGCGAGGUCUCCUAUGACCCACUCUAUGCUGUCUUCGCUGUCUUCGCCUUCACCUCGGUUGUGGACCUCAUCAUCGCUCUUCAGGAAGACAGCUAUGUGGUGGGCUUCAUGGAGUUCUACACCAAGGAGGGAGAGCCAUACCUGCGCACAGCGCACGGAGUCUUCAUCUGCUACUGGGAUGGCACUGUUCACUACCUCCUCUACCUGGCCAUGGCCGGCGCCAUCUGCAGAAGGAAGAGAUACCGGAAUUUUGGACUCUACUGGCUGGGUUCCUUCGCCAUGAGCAUCCUGGUGUUCCUUACAGGAAACAUUCUUGGCAAAUACAGCUCCGAGAUCAGGCCUGCCUUCUUCCUCACCAUCCCCUACCUGCUGGUGCCAUGCUGGGCUGGCAUGAAGGUCUUCAGCCAGCCCCGGGCGCUAACCCGCUGCACCGCCAACAUGGUGCAAGAGGAACAAAGAAAGGGACUCCUGCAGCGUCCGGCUGACCUGGCCCUUGUCAUAUAUCUCAUCCUUGCUGGCUUCUUCACUCUGUUCCGGGGCCUGGUGGUGCUUGAUUGCCCCACAGAUGCCUGCUUUGUCUAUAUCUACCAGUAUGAGCCAUACCUGCGGGACCCUGUGGCCUACCCUAAGGUGCAGAUGCUGAUGUACAUGUUUUAUGUCCUGCCUUUCUGCGGCCUGGCUGCCUAUGCUCUCACCUUCCCUGGUUGCUCCUGGCUUCCAGACUGGGCCUUGGUGUUUGCUGGAGGCAUCGGCCAGGCACAGUUCUCGCACAUGGGGGCUUCCAUGCACCUGCGCACACCCUUCACCUACCGUGUGCCUGAGGACACCUGGGGCUGCUUCUUCGUGUGCAAUCUGCUGUAUGCGCUGGGCCCCCACCUGCUGGCCUACCGUUGCCUUCAGUGGCCCGCAUUCUUCCACCAGCCACCACCCUCCGACCCCCUAGCCCUCCACAAGAAGCAGCAUUGAGAGAGCUGUGGACUCAGGACCCAGGACUCUGUUUACGUGCCCAGUCAGCCCUACCUGGGGAAGCGGGGGUUGGGUGUUUUAGAGACAGGAGGGACAUCUCCGGGUGUCUUUAGUCUUGGCUAUGGUAGUUUCAGUCCAGUGGGUGGGAUGGAGACCAACGACCAAGUGUUCCUGCAAGGAGAGCCUCCCACAGCUGUCACCAUGCUCCAACUCCCACACAAACGCUUCUACCCCUUCCAGAACUUACCCAUCAUCCCCCCAUGGAUCCUUUCAGUAAAAACCCUUUCAAUUUCCAAAA